ACAGCCCAGCGGCGGCCAUUCGCGGAAAAAGAGGCAGAGCCUGUGCCAGCUACAGCCUCCUCCGAGCCACCGCGGGCGGGCGGGACCGGCCUCUCCUCCCGCCUCGCCCCCACCCCCACCCACCUCUAUCCCAGUGUCUCCGUCUGAGGGUUUGUCCUGUUAAUGCGGGAUGAGCGAUCAGAAGAAGGAGGAGGAGGAGGAGGCGGCAGCGGCAGCGGCGAUGGCUACAGAAGGAGGGAAAACCUCUGAGCCAGAGAAUAACAAUAAAAAACCCAAAACCUCAGGCUCCCAGGACUCUCAGCCCUCUCCUCUGGCUUUACUGGCAGCUACUUGCAGCAAAAUAGGGACUCCUGGUGAAAAUCAAGCAACUGGACAACAACAAAUUAUUAUAGAUCCAAGUCAAGGAUUGGUGCAACUUCAAAAUCAACCACAACAGCUAGAACUGGUAACAACGCAACUUGCUGGAAACGCUUGGCAACUUGUUGCCUCCACUCCUCCUGCUUCAAAAGAGAAUAACGUUUCUCAACCAGCCUCUAGUUCGUCUAGUUCUUCCAGCAGUAAUAACGGGAGUGCAUCUCCUACAAAAACUAAAUCAGGUAAUUCUUCCACCCCUGGUCAAUUUCAAGUCAUACAAGUACAAAAUCCAAGUGGUAGUGUACAGUACCAAGUAAUUCCACAACUUCAGACAGUGGAAGGUCAACAAAUUCAAAUCAAUCCAACUAGUAGUUCAUCUCUACAGGAUUUGCAGGGUCAAAUUCAGCUCAUUUCUGCAGGUAAUAAUCAAGCUAUACUCACAGCUGCUAACAGGACAGCUUCUGGGAAUAUUCUUGCUCAAAACCUGGCAAAUCAGACAGUUCCGGUCCAAAUUAGACCUGGUGUUUCAAUACCACUGCAGUUACAGACUCUUCCUGGUACUCAGGCUCAAGUUGUAACAACCCUACCAAUUAACAUUGGAGGAGUGACUCUAGCUUUGCCAGUGAUAAACAACGUGGCUGCCGGAGGAGGGACUGGGCAGGUUGGCCAGCCUGCUGCUACUGCUGAUAGUGGGACUUCCAAUGGGAAUCAAUUAGUUUCCACACCCACCAACACCACUACUUCUGCCAGUACUAUGCCAGAAUCUCCCUCCUCCUCCACUACCUGCACAACCACUGCUUCAACGUCUUUGACAAGCAGUGACACAUUAGUGAGCUCAGCAGAUACUGGCCAGUAUGCAAGCACAUCAGCCAGUAGUUCUGAACGCACCAUUGAAGAAUCUCAAACACCUGCUGCUACUGAGUCUGAAGCCCAGAGCUCCAGUCAGCUUCAGCCUAAUGGAAUGCAGAAUGCACAGGAUCAAUCAAAUUCUCUUCAGCAGGUGCAAAUUGUAGGCCAACCUAUCUUACAGCAGAUCCAGAUCCAACAGCCUCAGCAACAGAUCAUUCAGGCUAUUCCACCACAGUCGUUUCAACUCCAGUCAGGGCAGACGAUUCAGACCAUCCAGCAGCAGCCUUUACAGAAUGUUCAACUUCAAGCAGUAAAUCCGACUCAGGUGCUUAUCAGGGCUCCAACUUUAACACCUUCAGGGCAAAUCAGUUGGCAAACUGUACAGGUUCAGAAUAUUCAGAGUCUUUCAAAUUUGCAAGUUCAGAAUGCUGGGUUAUCCCAACAAUUAACCAUCACCCCAGUGUCUUCAAGUGGUGGCACAACUCUUGCUCAGAUUGCUCCUGUGGCUGUUGCUGGUGCCCCAAUAACUUUGAAUACUGCCCAGCUUGCAUCAGUGCCUAACCUUCAGACAGUGAGCGUUGCCAACCUGGGUGCUGCAGGUGUUCAAGUGCAGGGAGUUCCCGUUACAAUCACUAGUGUUGCAGGUCAGCAGCAAGGACAAGAUGGAGUAAAAGUCCAGCAAGCUACUAUAGCUCCUGUAACUGUAGCAGUUGGAGGAAUUGCUAAUGCCACGAUAGGUGCUGUUAGUCCUGACCAACUCACACAAGUGCAUUUGCAGCAAGGCCAGCAGACUUCUGAUCAAGAGGUACAACCUGGCAAGAGGCUUCGAAGAGUUGCCUGUUCCUGUCCUAAUUGUAGGGAAGGAGAAGGAAGAGGCAGUAAUGAACCAGGAAAAAAGAAGCAGCAUAUCUGUCAUAUUGAAGGAUGUGGUAAAGUUUAUGGCAAAACAUCUCAUUUACGAGCACAUCUUCGCUGGCAUACUGGAGAAAGACCUUUUAUAUGCAACUGGAUGUUUUGUGGCAAAAGAUUCACACGGAGUGAUGAGCUCCAGAGACAUAGAAGAACCCAUACAGCAAAGCAGUUAUAAAGUGAACAUCAUGUUUACCCUUUCACCUUUCAAAGACUGCAGCUGCUAUAAAUCUAAUGUGUCUAAGUUUUACGUACACUUUUAAUACUCUGACAUAUAUGAUUAAUGGAUCUACAUAAAAAAUGUUUUGUGUGUGUUAUGAAAUGUUACAAUGUUGCAGAAUUAUAAAUUUCACUUGUUUUGAGAUCUGUUUGUACAUAUAUGUAUAUUUGCAUAUAUGAAUUUCCUUGAACUGCUAUAUAAUAUUUUAUCACAUGAGUCUACCACACUAUAUUAAUUCAUUCCCAUACUGUUUGAGGUUAUUGCUAGGGUUUGUGUGUGCUAUCACAAACUUAGUUGAUGAGAACAUGUGUGAGAAGUGGAAUUAUUGGAUCAUAGAGAAUGUGUAUGUUUGGUUUUGCUAGGUAAUGGCUAAAGAGUCUCUACAGUGGCUAUUUAACUAGCAGUGAUUGAUAGUUUCCACUUUGUGCUCACCAGUACCCAGUAGUGUCAGGCCUUGAAAGUUUUUUUCAAUCUAAAAUUGUUUCUUAUUUUAAAAAUUUGUGUUUUUCAUGGUUAUCCAUGAGAUUAAGCACCUUUCAUAUGUAUAUUAGUCAUUUAUGGCUUUGUUUUUUAAUUCUGGUUCUCAUUUUUUCUUUCAGAAGUUUUCCUUAUUUAUAUGAUUUAUAUGUUAUACUUUUCCCUUUCAAUAAAGGACUAGUGCUAGUCUUUUAUCUUUGUCAUACCUUUUGUCAUAUGGAAGUCUUACAUUUUUAUUUAGUCAAAUAUAAAUCUUUUCUUUUGUCUUUUGCUUUUUGUUUAUAAAUUUUUCUUCUGUCCCAAGGUCAUAAAGUCUCAAAAAACAAUUUCUUCUAAUAGCUUUAAAGUUUUAUUUUUGUAAGUUUGAUCUUUUAUUCGCUCAAGAUUCUUUUUGUUGAUGGAAUGAAAUGAGAAUACAAUUUUAUUUUUCUUUCAUAUGGAAAGCCCUUUCUUAAACAGCCCAUUCUGUCUCUAUUGAUUGUCCUCUUUUACAUAAUGUCUCCUUUAAGUGUGGUUCAAUUUCUGGUUUCUCUGUUUUGAAGUUUUUAUCUAUUUGCCAGUUCCUACACCAAUGCUCUUACUAUAUUAAUGACUGUGGUUUUAUAUUAAGCCUUGACUUCUUUUUGGGCAAUUUUCCUUCUUUCUUUAUUUUUUUUUCUUUUUUUGCCCAGAACACCUACCCUUUUCAGAAUAUUUAGAAUUUGGGACUCAGUAUUUCAUUAUUGAAUAAAUUAAUUUCAAUAAAUUAUUGAAUUAUACUUUAUACUUUAAACCUGUACCAAGAUACAUGUGGGACAAAGGGAGAAAUAAAACUGACAUUUCUAAAUCAGCUGCUAUAUUAUAGUCAGAUAUUUUGAAUAUAUUACUUCAUUUGAUUCUAACAACAGCAACACCGGCAUAGAAAUUAGCUCCAUUUUAAGAUUAGAAAGUAGUAUCAGAAAAGAAAAAAUUAUGAAAUCUAUUAAAAAUGGUAAAUAUAAAGUUAUUUAAUUUGAUAUACACAUAAAGUAGUAAUACAAAUGAGUACAGAUUGAGUACCCCUUGUCUGAAAUGCUUGGGACUAGAAAUGUUCUAGAUUUCGGAUUUUUUCAGAUUUUGCAUGUGCACAAUGCAAUACUUCGGGGAUUCAUUUUUGUUUCAUAUAUACCUUAUACAUAAAGACUGAAGGUAAUCUUAUACAAUAUUUUUAAUAAUUUUAUGUGUGAAAGUUUGUGUUAAGUACUUAUGUGUGGAAUUUUCUACUUGUGGGAUCGUGUCAACACUCAAAAAGUUUCAGAUUUUGGAGCAAUUUGGAUUUUAGAUUUUUGUAUUAGGGAUGCUCACCCUGUGUUAGUAUAGCGUCGCAAUCCCUGAAAAAGUUAGCAUUAUAGUAAAGCUCUGAAUUUUAAUUUUAAAAAAGAUAAUUUGAAAUCUUUCUGUAUAGUAUAUACACCAUUGACGUUGGCAAAUAUGAUUGAUUAAAAGUUAAUUCCAUACCAGUUGUUGAUAUCUGUUUUAGAAAAAUACUCUGCUAUUUAGGUCUGCAUGAAAGGAUGCAGUGUUUCCAUCCUGGAUUAGCAGUGGGAUAAAUUAGGGAAGCCAAGAAAAUUUUCUACUUUGUUUGAUUUGGAACCUCACAUUAUGAUUGCUUCAUUUUGUCUAAGAAAUGAUGAGUUGGUAAAGUCCCUCUCUCUUACACAUCCACACACUUGCAGAUACACAAAACAAAUUUAUUUAAGAAUUUAUAUAUACAUAUACUUCAAAACCAAAUAUUAUGAUUUGGGGCAUAUCUUUAAAAAAAAGAUUCACACCAUUAUUAUCUACUGGAUUGACAAUUCAUAAUCCAAUAUACUUUAAGCUUACUUUCAGUGGUUCAAACAUCUUAAAUAUAUCACACAUAAAAUUGUUUAAUUAAAACAGGUUGACACUAAAAAAUAUUAAUAUCAGUAUACUUAAAAUUGUUACUUUUAAAGAUUUAACAGAGUAACUCCUGUUUGUUAAAUUUGUCUAAAAGAAUAUGAAAAAAUAUAUUUUGAAAUAAGUAUUGAUUAAGCAUUUAAUAUGUUAAGUUGAAAGCCUUAACCAUUCGUAGCAACAACUAUGCUUUAUUUGAUGUCUAACCACUACUACAAAUAGAAACUUAUUGACUUGGCUAUGAAUGAAUGGAGUUAUUUGUAUUCACUGCUGAAAAUAGUGAUCUGUUUGCUUUUUAAAAAAAUUUGUAAAGGUUUUCAAAACAAUAUAUGCAUAUGGUAUUUAAAAAUGAAAUCACAGAAAAGUUUACUGUAAUAAGGAGGCUCUUUGCCCCACCCCAUCCUGCUUUCCAGAGAAUAUCAUAGCUAACUAUUUUAACUAUUUUUGCAUUUUUGUUCUUUCUAGGAUGACUGUCAUGUAUCUAAAUCAUAUACUUAAACACUGUUAUUUAUUGAUCUAUCAAUAUUUUAUACUAUCUAUUGAGUUCUUGCAUUUAGAAUUAAGGAUUUACUUCACUUUGCACCAUCUGAAGACAUUAAGAUUCUUUUGAAAAACUGUAUGCAGGCCAGGCAUUCUCUCUUAACUCACCACUCUAUUUCCAAUAAAGUUAGACAAUGCCUUUUCUUUUUUCUUGUAUUGUUUGACUUUACCUGAAAUAAUCUUUAGUUAUUUCAAGUUUUUAAGAACAAUGUGAAUUCCAGUCACAUUUUCCUUUUUUCUGGAGCCUUCCAUCUUUCUAAUGAACAUGAACAGUUUCUUCUGUAGACCUGUUCCAGGGGUAUUAUCUUGAGAUUUCUUCCCUUCUCUGUUCGUUUUAGAUCUCAUAUUGGUUCUCAAGAUCUCGUGUUUUCAUUUUUCUUGGUCUACUCUCUUCGUUGCUGGAAAACGUGCUGAAAUGCUUCCUAACGAAAAGCUUGGGGAAAUAAAUUUGUCUAAAGGAUUCUUUAUUUUCUCUUUCUGCUUAAUUUGGUUGUUUGGCUAAUACAGUAUUCUAGAUUGAAAAUUACAUUCUCUUAAAACAUUGUCACAGCUCUAUUUUCUUUCAUCUGUUUUAUCAACAAGAGGUUUGUUAUUUUUUCUUGUUUUUUUUUUCUGUAGGUGACCUGAUUUCUUCCCUGCAGCUUUAUUUUUAUUUUGAAAUAAUUUUAUACUUAGAGAAGAGUUGCAAAGCUAGCAUAGAGUUCGCAUAUCAUUCACCAAGCUUCCCUUAUUGUAAACUUCUUGUAUAACCACAGUACCUUAUGAGAAUUAAGAAAUUAACAUUGUUGCAAUACUAUUAAUUACACUUUCCACCAAUAUACCUUUUCUUUUCCAGGAUUCAGUCUGGAAUAACACACUGCAUUUGUUUGUCAUGUUUCCUUAGUCUCCUGCAAUCUGUGACUUUUCCUAGUCCUUUCCUUGUCUUUUAUCACCUGGACACAUUUGAAAGUGGUUUUGGUAUUUUUAGAAUGUCUGUCACAUUGGGUUUGUCUAAUGUUUUCUAAUGAUUAGAGUAAGAUUGUGAAUUGUCAUGAGAAGAAUAGCACAUUAGUGUCUUUCUCUUAUCAUAUAAGAGGAAGUAUGUAAUGUGAUUAUCUCAUUAUUGGUGAUGUUAACCCUGAUGUAUUGGUUAAUGUAGGGUGUGCCACAUUUCUUCACUGUAAAGUUACAGUUUCUCUCUUUCCAUAUUGUUUGUUAGAAGCAAGUCACUAAGUUCAGUCGACAUUCAGGGGGAAGAGAACUAAGCUUCACCUCCUGAAGGGAGAAGUAUCGAAGAAUUUGUGGACAUAUGUUAAAACCACCACAAUAAUUACUAUUUUAGAGGAGUUUGGGGGGCUUUUUUACAAAUAAAAUACUAAAGCUUCACUUUUAGCAUUCCUCAGUGGAUCUUGCCUGCAGCAGUUAUUACUGUGAUGUUUGAAAGGUCAUUUUCAAUUUUCCUUGUUCUUUGUACCACUUAUACUUUCUUCUCCAAUUAUUUAUGCAAUCAUUUAUUUACAUUGGUAUGGUCUCAUGAGUAGUUCUUUUGUUCUUUGGGUUAUAAUUCAAUACUAUCAUUUUCUUGCUCAAAUUGUUUCACCUUUGGCCAUUGGAAGGUCUUUCACAUUAGUUCCUGUGUCUUCUUGAAGUGCCCCUGUUUUGUUUUUAACGCUAAGGGCGCCUUUUAAUCUGUGGUGUGCUGCUAAUUUCAUAAUGCUGUAUCUGAGAAUAGAUUUUUAUUUGUUGUGCUAAUGACUUGUACUCUGGGUCACCUCUCUCCCUCUCUCUCUCUUUCUCUGUCUCUCUCUCUCUGUCUCUCUGGGCUCUUAGUAGACAUAUUUUGGAAUCUCUAGGGUUUUUUUUUUUUUUUUGGUCUUACAGUUUUUCUCUUAUAUCUUUUGUCUCAUUACCAUUUUAUUUUCCAUGAAAUUUUUUAAGUUUACUUUCAGAUAUUUCUAUUGAAUUGCAUUUUAAUUUCCAAUAGUGUAUUCCAUCAUUGUUGGUGGGUUUUGUUUUGUUUUACUGCAUUUUGUUCUCAUUGUAUGGAUGCAGGUGCUUGCUGAAAUUAUCUCAGUUUUUUAAUCUAGAAUUUUAUGUUUCCUCCAGGAUGAUUUUUUUGUCUGUAUCUUUUUCCAGUGUUGUAGGCGUUCCUGAAUUGUCCAGUGAUUCUUUGUUUUUGUUCAAGUUGAUGAUGAUGAUGAUGAUGAUGGUGGUGGUGGUGGUGGUGGUGGUGGUGGUGGUGGUCAUGGUGGUGAUUUGAUGAAAUCUUAAGUGAAAGAUUUUGAAAACUUUAUGAGCUAGUGGCGUUUUGUUUUGGUUUUUUUGAGACAGGGUCUCUGUCUGUCACCAGGCUGGAGUUCACUGGCACGAUCACAGCUCACUGCAACCUCCUCCACCUCCCAGGCUCAAGUGAUCCUCACACCUCAGCCUCCCGAGUAGCUGGGACCACAGGUGCAUGCCACCACACCUGGCUAAUUUUUCUAUUUUUUGCAGAGACAGAUUUUUCUCAGUGUUGCCCAGGCUGGUGUUGAACUCCUGAGCUCAAGCAAUCCAUCCUCCUCAGCCUCCUGGAGUGUUGGGAUUAUAGGUGUGAGCCACUGCCUCUGCCAAGCUAGUGGCUUUUAUUUUAGGUAACUGGGUGGAACACUGUGUUACACUGGAAGAUGCCUAAUUACCAAAAUACAAUAAUAUGCUGUGCAACCAUGUUUUUUUAAGAUACAAAUCUUUAAUAUUAACAUUUUGCCCCAAUUUUUUGAUAGUAGUUAUAGUCUAUGUAUGGACUUUAAUUUUGUUUUAUGUUCCAUGUCUCCCUCCCAGCAGAAGACAUUGACUGUCUUCUAGAACAUAUUCUCUUCCUUGACAAUUUAUUUUCUAGUUUGCAGACAUUUGAUAUAAUCAUUGUUUUGCUGAUGGACUUCCUUUCCUUUUUUUUUUUUUUUGUUAUUGUAGAUUUAACCCUUUUAUGCCUUUACUAUUAUUUUAAUGGGUGUCUCAGUGGGGAGAAUAAACAAACACAUGUAAUCAUGCUGCUCUCUUAAACUUUAAAGGGUUACAUUUAGCCAGGUGCAGUAGUGCACACCUAUAGUCCCAGCUACUCAGGAGGCUGAGGCGGGAGAACUGCUUGUGCUAGGAGUUCGAGGCUAUAGUGCCUAUGAUCCCGUGAAUAGCCACUGCACUCCAGCCUGGGCAAUAUAACAAGACCCCGUCUCUUAAAAAAAAAAUACUGAUAACUUGGAAAUACUAUAAUGAUACAACUAAAUGGAUAAUGUCUAUAAUAACGAUGUCAUAUAGAUAUGCACACUUUUAUGUUACAUGUGUUAAUAUAGUGUACUUUGUGAAUAUUUUAUUGUAGAUACUUUGCCUACUUACUGGACUGUUUUAUUUGCCAUUCAUAAUCCACUUAGAAGUAAGGCAAUCUAGGGAUGAUUUUUAGCAACUAGUGUUAUAGGGAUCUUUAACCAGAUCUCAAAUUCUUUUUCACCAGCUAAGAAAAAAUCCUUUUCAAAAGAGCCCCUAAAAAGUCUUGUGCAACUGCAGUAUAGGUUCUUUAUAAUAUAUGACGACUUAGUGUUUUAGCCAAGAUACAAUUUUAUAUAAAGUUAAAUGUAUUUAUAAUUGUAUCAAUAAUUAUAAGCUUAAGUGGAAAUGAAACAGAUUCUGUAAAAUUCAUUUGGGAAUGAAACUUCAAUUUUUUUAACAAAAUAAGGAAUAUUUGAUCAAAACAGAUGAAACAGAAAACUCCAUCAAUUUCGUUGAAGUUUUCUCACAGAAUUUUGUUGUUGUUGUUGUUGCUGAGACCAUGUCACCCAGGCCAGAACGCAGUGAUGUGAUCAUAGCUCACGGCAGCCUUGACCUCCUGGGCUCAAGCAGUCCUCCCACCUCAGCUGCCUGAGUAGCUGGGACUUGCAGGCCUACACCACUACACCUAGCUAAUUUUUUUUUUUUUUUAAAGGUGGGUUUUUGCUAUGUUGCCCAGGCUGGUCUUUUUUUCUUUUUUCUUUUUUUUUUUUUUUUUUUUUUUUGAGAUGGAGUCUCGCUCUGUCACCCAGGCUGGAGUGCAGUGGCAUGAUCUUGGCUCACUGCAAGCUCCGCCUCCUGGGUUCAUGCCAUUCUCCUGCCUCAGCCUCCCGAGUAGCUGGGACUACAGGCGCCCGCCACCACACCCGGCUAAUUUUUUGUAUUUUUAGUAGAGAUGGGGUUUCACUGUGUUAGCCAGGAUGAUCUCAAUCUCCUGACCUUGGAUCCACCCGCCUCGGCCUCCCAAAGUGCUGGGAUUACAGGCGUGAGCCACUGUGCCCAGCCCCAGGCUGGCGUUAAACUCCUAUCCUCAAGUGAUCCUCCCACCUCAGCCUCUCAAAGUGCUGGGAUUAUAGGUGUGAGCCACAGUGCCCAGCCCCAGAAUUUUCUUAUAUAAAUGUUUUAAUUAGUAUGUGAAACAUCAAAACUGUUGCCCUUUGUGUCCACUGUUGGCCAGAAUGGACCAAGUUAUCUACAACUUGUCUGUUCCAUUGACUACACUAAAAACUCUGGACAAGUUUACUUAUUUGUUUUCUUAAGUAUCUAAAUGAGGACAAUGAAAAGCAAACUAUAGCAGGCAAUUGAGAAAUGAAGUGAAAACUUGAAUUUGAAUAACAGUGUAUCAUAUGUGUUCAUUUCAUAGAGAUCUUUUUCCCUCCUUUGUCUCCCAGGUUUAACCCUGCGGGCACUGCAUAGCAGGUGCAGGUAGCAAACAAUCUAAGAGAAACCUCUUGUAUCUAACCAGAAAAGCAAGAAAAGGGGCCUUUUGCUCCAAAACCAGUUCCAUUUGCAGAUUACACUGAAAUAGUAGCAGCUUAGGCACCAAAAAAUCUCUAGAAAAUACCCAUAUCUCUGGCUAGGGGAACUAGAAAAUAGAGUCUGUUUUCCAAGAAAUCUGAGGUAAAUCAACAUCAUUUUUCUGUCUUGCCACUUCUACUCUGAAGGUGGUCCCAGUCGUGGUGUAAGUGCAGAACAUUAUGGGAGCCCCCAGUAACUUGGCUUUUCUAGCCGGAGGAACUAGAAGGUGAGACAACUGGAGGUUGGAAAGGCAUAGGGGAAAUUUUGAGAGCGAUAUAAAAGAUGCUUCCUAAUUCUGUGUGUAGAUCAAAAGAAGUCCUGGGUUCAACCUUGCACUGGGCUCAACCUUGAGCAUUGCAUGCACAGCACAGACACAAAGAACCACAGCAAAGGCCUCAAGAACUAAACAUCUUAAAAACCACCAUCCAAUUCCCAGCAUGUGCUGAGCAGAGACAAAAAGCAUAACAAAGCCUUUGAAAAGUGAAUUAAUGUUGGAACUGCUGCUCAAAGAGGGCAAGAUGGAACUUUUAGUCUGAACCUAAACGGGUUGAGUGCCUGCUAAAACAAAAACAUUUUCCAGAGAAUUUUUAACAGGGCCUAAAGUCUCUGCAAUAUAAUGUCCAAAAUGUCCGGGAUACAGUCCAAAAUUACUCAACAUACUAUGAGCCACGUAAAGCUGACUUUUUAUUAAGAGAGAAGAUAACAGAUGUCAAGAUGAUCUAGAUUUCGGAAUUAUCAGAUAAGACCUUUAAAGCAGCUCUUAUAGCCAUGAUCCAUGGACUAAAGAUAAGCGUGACUGAAAUCAAUGGAAAGGCAGAAGUUUUUAGCAGAGAAAUCUGCUAUAAAAACUAUAAAAAAGAACUAAAUAGAAAUUUUAGAUUUAGAAAAAUACAAUAUUAAAAGUAAGUUUAUCAGAUGCUCAGUAGCUAAGUGGAGAUAAUAGAGGAAAGAGUCAGUGAGAUUGAAGAUAGACCACUGGAAAUUAUAAAAUCUGAAGAAUUGAAAGGAAGAAGAUUGGGGAGUCAGAAAAAACUGGAUUGCAGGGAUCUGUGGGACAAUAAUAAAAGGUCUUAAAUUUGUGUCAUUGGUCUCCCAGAAGGAAAGGAAAAAUACUGCUGUAAGACAAAAUUUGAAGAAAUAAUGGCUGGGACUUCCCAUGUUAGGUAUAAUAGGUUCAGGAAGUUCGUUGAAUCCCAAGCAGAAACUAAAAGAAAACAAUAUCAUAUUGUAAUCAAUCUGCUGUAAAUCAAAGAUAAAAAAUCUUGAAAGAAGCCAGAAGAGAAGGACACAUUAUAUACCGGGGAACAAAAAUUCAAAUUAUGGCGGAUUUCUUCUUAGAAACUAUGGAGGACAGAGAAAGAAAAGAACUAUCAACUAUCAACUCACCAUUUUAUGUCCAAGGAAAAUAUCCUCAAAACAGUAUAGUAACAAGAGCAAAGUAAAGAUACUUCCAAAGGAAAACUAAGAGAAUUUGCUGCUAUCAGAUCUGCCUCAAUAGAAAUGCCAAGGAAGUUCUUCAAGGUAAAAUUAAUUAUACCAGAGAGAAAUUUGAAAUUGAAUAAUGAAGGAAGGGCAAAAAAUAAAAAUAAAUCGUCUUUUCUGUUUUCUCAGCCACUUGCCAAAAGAAAUGCUAAAUACCUGGGUAAAUAGAGCAGACUGUUUUUCCUCUGCUGAAAUUCUUUAACAUAUGUCUAUUUACAGUUAAAAAAAAUUAACAUUGUCUUGUAGAUAGUCAUUGUAUGUUGAUGUAAUACAUAUGGCCAAUAUAACAGAAAGGGAGGGUAAGGAAGCCAAUAGUUAAAAAGCUGCUUUGUUUUACUCUGAUAAUAUAGAAGUUGUUAUAUAUAUUUUGAAAAGUUAGAUAUAUACCAACCACUACAGAGAGGGUGGGUGGAGAUACUCCCCUAAAUGUCUCCUAUAUAUAGGACUGAUAAUUAUUAUAGACUUUAAUAAUUUUGUAAAUUAAAUGAGAAUACUAAACAACAUUCAAAUAUAGGUUGAUAAUCUCUAAUUCACAGCGCUCCAAAAUCUGAAACUUUUUCAGCACCAGCAGGACGCUCAAAAGAAAUAGUCAUUGGAGUGUGUUGUUUUUCAGUUUAGGAUGCUCAGUCAGUAUGUAUUCUGCAAAUAUUCAAAAAUCUGGGAAAAAAAUCCAAAAUCUGAAACACUUAUAGGCCCAAGCAUUUCAGAUAAGGGAUACUUGACUGUCAUCUGAAAAAAAUGGAGAAAAGGGAAAAUAGAAGCAUGAAAAACAGACAAUUUAAAAACAGAUGAUAAAAUGAUAGACUUAAAAUCUAAUCAAAUCAAUCAUUACACUAAAUGCAAGUGGUAUAAAUUAUACUAAUCCAAAGGGAGAUACUGUCCAAUGACAUUUUUUAAAAAGGAUCCAGCUGUAUACUCUGGAUAAAGAGAGUAUCUGAAUAACACUCCACUUUAAAGAAUAUCCCAGCAGAAUGUGUAUUUUAUUCAAGAGCACAUGGAACAUUCACAGAGGUAGACCAUAUUCUGGACCAUGAAACACUCCUUAACAAAUUUGAAAUAAGAAUCAGACUGGCAUGGUGGCUCAUGCCUGUAAUCCCAGCACUUUGGGAGGCCAAGACAGGUGGAUCACCUGAGAUCAGGAGUUUGAGACCAGCCUGGCCAACAUGGUGAAACCCCACCUCUACUAAAAAUACAAAAAUUAGCUAGGCAUGGUGGCAUGUGCCUGUAGUUCCAGCUAAUUGGAAGGCUGAGACAGGAGAAUUUCUGGAACCCUGGAGGUGGAGGUUGCGGUGAGCUGAGAUUGCACCAUUGCACUCCAGCCUGGACGACAGAGUGAGAUUCCAUGUGAAAAAAAAAAAAAUCAUACGAAGUAUGUUCUCACAUCAUUAAGCUAGAAAUCAAAUAACAAAAAUAUCUAGGAAAUCCCUAAAUAUCUAGAAAUCAAACAACACAUGGGCCAAGAAAAAGUUUCAAGGGAAAUUAGAAAAUAUUUCCAAUUAAAUGAAAAUACACCAUAAAAUUUGUGGGAUGCAGGUAAAGCAGUGCUUAGAGGAAAUUCGUAGCAUUAAAUGCUUUUACUGGUAAAAAAAGAAAGGUCCUCAGUCAAUAGUCUAAACUUCCACCUUAGGAAACUACAAAAUGAAGAGCCAAUUAAAUUCAAAAUAAGAAGUUGGGAAAUAAUAAAGAGUAGAAAUAAAAAGAAUGCUAUGCAUAACUCUACAACCUAAAUUUGAGGACUUAGAUAAAAUGGAACAACUCCUUGAAAGAUACAAGCUACCAACACUGGCUCAAGAAGAGAUAGAUAGCAUGAAUGCUCCUAUAUCUGUUAAAGAAAUUGGAUUUGUAAUUUUAAACUUUUGACAAAAGAAAACUCUGGGCCCGUAUGGUUUCAUUGACAAAUUCUACCAUUUAAGGAAUAAAUAAUACCAAAUUCUACAAUUUCUUUCAGAAAAUAAGGAACACUUCUCAACUUAUUCUAUGAGGCUCACAUUAUCAUGAUACCAAAGAAAAAAACUUAGACCAAUAUCGUAAGUAUAGUUGUCAAAAUUUUCAACAAAAUACUAGCAAAUCCAGCAAUAUAUAAAAAGGAUAAUGCAUUGUUACGUAGUACAGUUUAUUCCAAGAAUGAAAAGCUGUUUGAAUAUUUGAAAAAGUCAAUGUAAUUCACUAAUAAUGACAAAAGAAAAAAAAUCACAUGACAGCAAACACACAAUAAAUAUUUGGCAAAAUUCUGCAUAUAUUUCUGUAAAAAUUCUCAGCAAACUGAGUUGAAGGAAACAUCAUUAACUGGGUAAAGGGCAUUUGCUAGAAAUCUGCAGUUAACAUCAUUCUUAAUGAUGAAGGACCUUUUGCUUCCCUGUGGAAUCAGGAACAAGGUAAAGACAUCUGAUUUUACCAUUCUUAUUCACCAUAGUACUGGAAUUUCUACCCAGUGCAGUAAAGCAGGAAAAUGUCAUAAAAGACAUACAGAUUCUAAUAGAAGAAAUAAAACUAUCUUUAUUUGCAGACACCAGGUUGUCUGUAUAGCAAAUCCGUGGUGCCUACCAAAAAGCUUUUUGAACUAGUGAGUUUGGCAAGGUUGCCAGAUACAGGAUAAAUGUACAACAGUGAAUUGUAUUUCUACAUCCUAGCAGUGAAUAACGGGAUAUAAGUAGUUUAUAAAAAGAGUGCCAUUUGUAAUAUGAUGAAAACAGUGAAACAUUUUGCCAUAAAUCUAACAAAAUAUAUGCAAGACAUGUAAGCUAAAAACUAAAACAUUGAUGAAAGAAUGCAAUGAAGAACUACAUUAAUGCAGAGAUACACAUUGUAUUCAAGGAUUGGAUGGCCCAAUAUUGUUUCCAUGUAAUUUCUCCCCAAACAUAUCUGCAGAUUCAGUAUAAUCCUUCUCAUAAUUCCAGCAGCAUUUUUAUAGAUAACAAGCUGAUUCUAAAAUUAUAUGAAAGGCAAAGCAAUUAGAAUAGCCAAAACAGUUUCAAAAAUAACAUAAUUGGCUGAUUUACACUGCAUAAUUUUAGGUGUUCCUGUAAAGCUACACUAAUCAACACUGUGUAGUUUUGAAGGACACAUGGAUAAGUAAGACAGAAUAUAGAGUCCAGAAAUUCCCCUCCACACACAGGGUGCAAAAACAGUUCAGUAAAGAAAAAGUAGCGUUUUCAAUAAAUUGUAUAGAAGAAUUAGCCAUAUGCAAAACCUUUAACCUACAUAUCUCAAGUCUUUUACAAAAACUAACUCCAAGUGAUUCAGAGACUUAAAUCCAAAACCUAAAACAACAAAGCUUUUUGAAUAAAAUAUAGGACAAAAUCUUUGCAGCCUUGAGAUAGGCUACGAGUGCUUUAACACAACUCCGAAAGUGUAAUCCAUAAAAGAAAAAAUCAGUAAAUAGGACUUGAUGAAAACUAAAAACUUUUGCUCUGUGAUGGAUCCUGUUAAGAGAAUGAAAACUCUUAACAGAUACAGAUACAGACUGGGAGAAAGUGUUUGAAAAUCACAUACCUGACAAAGUGCUUUUAUGCUGAACACCUUAAGAAGUUUUAAACUCAGUGUAAACAAAUUUAACAGUUUUUUUUUUUUAAAUGAGCAAAGGAUUUGACACUUCACCAGAGAACAUAUGUAUGUGACGGAAAAGUGCAUGAAAAGAUGUCUGAUAUCAUCUAUUAGGGAAAUGGAAAAUAAAACCAUAAUGCAAUACUACUGUACACCUAUUAGAAUGGCUAAAAUCAAAAGCAAGAACCAUGAGAACAUGGUAACUGCAAGUACUGGUGAGGAUGCAGAGCAAUUGGAAUUCUCAUAUAUUGCUGGUGGGAAUGCAAAAUGACACACUGCCUUUGGAAACUAGUUUGGCAUUUUCUUAUAAACAUGCAAUUACCAUAUGAUCUAGCAAAUCUACUUCUGAGUAUUUACCCAAGAGAAGUAAGAACUGUGUUCACACAAAAAAAGCUGUGAGUGUGCAUGUGUGUGUGUGUGGCAGAUUUAUUUAUUUAUUACUCAAAAUUGGAAGUAACCCAAAUGUCCUUCAGCUGGUGAAUGGAUAAAAAUAUCCAUACAUUGGAGUACUACUCCCCAACAUAAAGGAAUGAAUUAUUAAUAAACAGCCACAUGGAUGAAACUCAGAUGCAUUAUGCUAAGUGAAAGAUUUCAGAAUCAAAAGACUGCAUAAUAUAUGAUAUCAUUUAUGUGAUAUUCUGGAAAAAUCAAAACUAUAAGGACAGAGAACAGAUUUGUGUUUUCUAGGGCAUAAGCAAGGAGGAGGGAGAGUUCAACUACAAAGAGACACUACAAAGGAAUUUUUGGAAGUGAUAGCAACUCUUCUGUGUGUUUAUUUUGGUGGCGAUUAUGUGACUGAAUGCAUUUGUCAAAACUCAUAGAACUCUAUACCAAAAAAAUGAAUUUUACUGUAUAUAAAUUAAAACAUAAAUGUUAAAAAAGUGGAGACAAACUCAUUUUGAGAGACUACAGUGUAAAAAGGGAGAGAGAUUUACUAUUUUAUAUUUUAAGAAUUCAGAACAGUUUUCUGUUAAGCCUCAUGUGCAUGCCUCAGUAUCAGGCAAACACUUCUGUUAACUCUGCCAAGGAUAAUAGGAUUUAGAGCCAAAGGGACUCCUGAAAAUUAUUUUGUGCAACCCCAUCAUUUCAUAAAUAAGUAAACUGAAGGCUCAAGAGGCUAAUUGUCUUCCAAGGCUCUAAAUGUAGUUACUCUUGCUGCUUUCUAGAUUUUCUCUUUGUCUUUGUCUUUCAGCAGUUUGAUUAUAAUGUGACUCGAUGUGACUCUCUGCAUUUAACCUACUCGGAGUUCAUUGAGCUUCUUGGAUAUGCAGAUUAUUAUUUAUUUAUUUUUUUUUCAAAUUGGGGAAGUUUUUACCUAUUUUUCAAAUAUUCUUUCUUUAAACACCUUGGAACUAAUGAGUCUCUCAGCCUGUGCUGAAAGGUUCUGUGUGCAUGUUGCAGCUUGCCUUCAGCACUCAGCCAGUCAUUUGACAUCUCUGCCUUAGCCUUCACUUUCUGCUUACCUAGAGCCUCAGGAUUAGGCACAGAUUAGUUAGGGCCUUCUCAUGCUAUUCUGAGCAGGCUCACAGCACUAAACGUGUGUGACCUUCUAAACAUGUAUGACCUUCUAGAUUCCUGUGUAUAUGUCACAGGUUUUUAAAGCUCUUCUGAAUCUCUUAGCUCUCAGCUAGCUUUUCCUUUAAAGCCUUUUGGUUAGUCUAUUGUUUGUCCCAAUUAUUAUCCCCUGUCUUGGGCAUCCAUGAAGUUAAAAUACUUGCUUCUAAUUGUUUUAGACAAACACAUGCCCUGCCUUACAUCUGGGAGAAGGCAUUUCUCAUGGGGCUACUUCACAGAGUCAGAUUAAAUAUGACAGUUUUAUAAGUGGAGUCUUCAGGGAAUGAUUAUUUGGGAAUUAGGCUUUGAAAGAGCCUCAGCUGUGUUCCACCCCCUCUAGUGGCUGCCAGAUGGUGCCAAGAAUUCAGGCUGUUAUUUUUCAAGGCUGCCACAGAGGUGGGGAGUGGAAAAUGAGACUAGUAAGUUAAAAUACUACAAAGCUUGCUGUUCUUACAGAAAUUCAGCCAUUUUUCUUGAAUAAACACUUCCAUGGAUUGCUGCAAGCCUUGAUUAAUUGCCAGAAUCUGAAAUGGUUGCUUUUGACAGUUUUUUUCCCAUAGGUUUUUGUUGCUUUUAUGGAAGAGCAAAGUUUUGGAGGUUCUUCACCAUGGUCAGUGACAUCAUUUCUUGGUUUUGCUCUUGCCCCCUCUUUCUUUCUGAAGCAUCAUAAGGAUUAGAAUGAUCCUUGUGUUGAUGAGUUCUCUUUGUGACAUGUUGAAUGAUGCUGUCUGUGGCACAUCCAGGAAAUGUCUAAUUCACAGCUGAGUUUCGGAAUCUGGAUCUUGAUGUAGUCAUCUAUUUAUAGAUGAUAGUUAAAACAAAGUGGAUUAAAUAGCCUAAAUAAAGCAUUUAUAAUGAAAUAA